CUCUUCUGCCCAUUGAGCAGUCAAAGAACUGAAAGUCCUUAUAAGCCUGUGCACCUGGGCCUGGGCCCUACAGAUAAGGUAGCUGCUAUUGCUAUGGCCCGCAUCAUUGACCUGGUGCCCUGGGACGAUGGCUCCACACAUGUGUAUGCCUCCCCGGCCAUCCUGCUUCCCAUGGAGCGGCAGCGCAACCAGCUGGCGGGCGUGAAGCAGCAGCUCUACCACCCAGCCCUGCCCACCCUGCGCCACAUGGACAGGGACACCGUCAAGGCCUGCCUUCCUGAUGAGCACUGCCAGUCCACCACCUACUGCCGCAAAGAUGAAUUUGACAACGCCCAUUUUACACUCCUUGGGGUCCCCAACAAACCCCUGCAGUGUUUGGACAUCACCGCCACAGGCCAGAAGCUUCGCAACAGGUACCACGAGGGAAAGCUGGCGCCCAUCGCGCCAGGCAUCAACCGAGUGGACUGGCCCUGCUUCACGCGCGCCAUCGAGGACUGGUCCCACUUCGUGUCCUCGGCCGGGGAGUUCAAGCUGCCUUGCCUGAGGAAGCGAGUACUGCCUCAGCCAGAACCCCAGCCUGGACCGCUACGGACAGAAGCCCCUGCCUUUCGACUCCCUGAACACUUUCCGAAGCUUCGGCUCCAGCUACAGGUAGGGGAACGGUCCUGUCCCGCCCCACAGCCAACCACGUUCUCAUCCGACUGCUGGGGACAGCCUCGGGGCUCCCUGACUCUGAAACCCCCCUGCCCCAGCGAGGCCUGGCGAGGAGGAGGGGCCCUCCUGGGAGGGCGCGAGCUGCUUCGCUCUGGAGAGAUCCGCCCCUGGCAAAUGUGCAGCCCACUGGGGUGGGGGUGGACGCGGGAGGGGGUCCACAUCCCACCAGGUUUGACUGGAGGAGGCCAAAAGGAUAGGGCGAGGAUGUUAACUAGAAGGAGAGAAAACAGACAAAUAAGAAACACAAGGGAGAGAGCCGAGAAUCUGCCUUUUAGGGUGCGGAGAGGCCCUAAGGGAGGGGGCUAAGUGGUCUUCCCGGCAGGGUCGCCCCACAAGUAAAGAGAUAAGAUAAGAACAAGAGUUCUUAUCUCCAAGAUAAGCACCUCUUGCAAGAGGUUGCAGGAUACUCAAACAUUUUCAUAACUAAGCCAUCUCUCACCCUCCCGGCCCCACUUUGUACACUCCAGCCAGACUAGACUCCCCCGAAACCCAGCAGACCAAGCACUCUUCACACCUUUGCCUGUGCUGUUUCAGCGCCUAGAUGGCCCUUCCUCCUCUGCCUGGAAAACUCCUUCGUGCCAUUAUUAUUAUUAUUAUUAUUAUUAUUGAGACGGAGUCUCACUCUGUCGCCCAGGCUAGAGUGCAAUGGCCUGAUCUCAGCUCACUGCAACCUCCGCCUCCCGGGUUCAAGCAAUUCUCCUGCCUCAGCUUUCUGAGUAGCUGGGAUUACAGGUGCGCAUGACCAAGCUUGGCUAAUUUUUGUAUUUUUAGUAGAGAUGAGGUUUCACCAUGAUGGUCAGGCUGGUCUCGAACUCCUGACCUUAUGAUCCACCCACCUCAGCCUCCCAAAGUAUUGGGAUUACAGGCGUGAGCUACAGUGCCCGGCCUCCUUCAUGCUCUUCAAAGCCCAGCCCAGAUGUGCCAUCCUCCUUGAAGUCUUCCCCCACCCUCUGCCUCUCCCCACCGGCUCACACUCCCUCCCAUUGGUCACUACCUUUGUGUCCCUGAGUAUCGAGUGCAAUACUCAGACUAUUGCACUGUCAUUAUUGACAGAAACCAGCCUUCCCGUCUCCCACACGGGGAAACGUUUCUGGGUUUUGCUACCAUAUGAUGCCUAACAGAGUAGGUUCACUAAAUGAUUGAAAAAUGGGUGAAGCUGUUCAUAGUUAGGUAUCAAUGGGAGAGAAGGAUGAGGCACAGUCAAAGGAGGGAGGUUAGCUUGAAAGCUAAGGAGGACAGCUGAAAAUACAGAAAACAGGGAGCCACUGAAGUCUCCUGAGCCACAUAGAGGCUGGCUGGAAGCUGUGUUUUCAGAUCCUAGAGGGGAAAAGCCUGAUUUUUCCCCUAGGACACCCUGGAAACCCCCACCUCACCCCUACUUCUCUCCACAGUCGUGUCAACUACCUGACCCCCUGGCAUUAAUCUCUGGAAAGGAGGCUGACUCCCAGGCUGCCGGACGGUGCCACCUCAGGUCCCCUGGCCAGACAGAGGACUUAUGGUGGCACCAGCCAUCUCCCCAGGAGUUCAGCCUAACUAGAAAUAAACCUAAUGCUCCCUUAGAGACACA